GGCCUAAGGCUGGGGGCCGACGGCGGCGGCAGCAGGGAGCUGGGAAGCGGAGAAGCCGGGAGCGCGGGGCUCAGUCGGGGGGCGGCGGCGGCGGCGGCUCCGGGGAUGGCGGCGGCUCCGCUGCUGCUGCUGCUGCUGCUCGUGCCCGUGCCGCUGCUGCCGCUGCUGGCCCAAGGGCCCGGAGGGGCGCUGGGAAACCGGCAUGCGGUGUACUGGAACAGCUCCAACCAGCACCUGCGGCGAGAGGGCUACACCGUGCAGGUGAACGUGAACGACUAUCUGGAUAUUUACUGCCCGCACUACAACAGCUCGGGGGUGGGCCCCGGGGCGGGACCGGGGCCCGGAGGCGGGGCAGAGCAGUACGUGCUGUACAUGGUGAGCCGCAACGGCUACCGCACCUGCAACGCCAGCCAGGGCUUCAAGCGCUGGGAGUGCAACCGGCCGCACGCCCCGCACAGCCCCAUCAAGUUCUCGGAGAAGUUCCAGCGCUACAGCGCCUUCUCUCUGGGCUACGAGUUCCACGCCGGCCACGAGUACUACUACAUCUCCACGCCCACUCACAACCUGCACUGGAAGUGUCUGAGGAUGAAGGUGUUCGUCUGCUGCGCCUCCACAUCGCACUCCGGGGAGAAGCCGGUCCCCACUCUCCCCCAGUUCACCAUGGGCCCCAAUGUGAAGAUCAACGUGCUGGAAGACUUUGAGGGAGAGAACCCUCAGGUGCCCAAGCUUGAGAAGAGCAUCAGCGGGACCAGCCCCAAACGGGAACACCUGCCCCUGGCCGUGGGCAUCGCCUUCUUCCUCAUGACGUUCUUGGCCUCCUAGCUCUGCCCCCUCCCCUGGGGGGGGAGAGAUGGGGCGGGGCUUGGAAGGAGCAGGGAGCCUUUGGCCUCUCCAAGGGAAGCCUAGUGGGCCUAGACCCCUCCUCCCAUGGCUAGAAGUGGGGCCUGCACCAUACAUCUGUGUCCGCCCCCUCUACCCCUUCCCCCCACGUAGGGCACUGUAGUGGACCAAGCACGGGGACAGCCAUGGGUCCCGGGCGGCCUUGUGGCUCUGGUAAUGUUUGGUACCAAACUUGGGGGCCAAAAAGGGCAGUGCUCAGGACUCCCUGGCCCCUGGUACCUUUCCCUGACUCCUGGUGCCCUCUCCCUUUGUCCCCCCAGAGAGACAUAUGCCCCCAGAGAGAGCAAAUCGAAGCGUGGGAGGCACCCCCAUUGCUCUCCUCCAGGGGCAGAACAUGGGGAGGGGACUAGAUGGGCAAGGGGCAGCACUGCCUGCUGCUUCCUUCCCCUGUUUACAGCAAUAAGCACGUCCUCCUCCCCCACUCCCACUUCCAGGAUUGUGGUUUGGAUUGAAACCAAGUUUACAAGUAGACACCCCUGGGGGGGCGGGCAGUGGACAAGGAUGGCAAGGGGUGGGCAUUGGGGUGCCAGGCAGGCAUGUACAGACUCUAUAUCUCUAUAUAUAAUGUACAGACAGACAGAGUCCCUUCCCUCUUUAACCCCCUGACCUUUCUUGACUUCCCCUUCAGCUUCAGACCCCUUCCCCACCAGGCUAGGCCCCCCACACCUGGGGGACCCCCUGGCCCCUCUUUUGUCUUCUGUGAAGACAGGACCUAUGCAACGCACAGACACUUUUGGAGACCGUAAAACAACAACGCCCCCUCCCUUCCAGCCCUGAGCCGGGAACCAUCUCCCAGGACCUUGCCCUGCUCACCCUAUGUGGUCCCACCUAUCCUCCUGGGCCUUUUUCAAGUGCUUUGGCUGUGACUUUCAUACUCUGCUCUUAGUCUAAAAAAAAUAAACUGGAGAUAAAAAUAA